AGCGCGAGCCCCGCCGCCGCCGAGCAUGGACGACCCCGACUGCGACUCCACCUGGGAGGAGGACGAGGAGGAUGCGGAGGACGCGGAGGACGAGGACUGCGAGGACGGCGAGGCCGCCGGCGCGAGGGACGCGGACGCAGGGGACGAGGACGAGGAGUCGGAGGAGCCGCGGGCGGCGCGGCCCAGCUCGUUCCAGUCCAGAAUGACAGGGUCCAGAAACUGGCGAGCCACGAGGGACAUGUGUAGGUAUCGGCACAACUAUCCGGAUCUGGUGGAACGAGACUGCAAUGGGGACACGCCAAACCUGAGUUUCUACAGAAAUGAGAUCCGCUUCCUGCCCAACGGCUGUUUCAUUGAGGACAUUCUUCAGAACUGGACGGACAACUAUGACCUCCUUGAGGACAAUCACUCCUACAUCCAGUGGCUGUUUCCUCUGCGAGAACCAGGAGUGAACUGGCAUGCCAAGCCCCUCACGCUCAGGGAGGUCGAGGUGUUUAAAAGCUCCCAGGAGAUCCAGGAGCGGCUUGUCCGGGCCUACGAGCUCAUGCUGGGCUUCUACGGGAUCCGGCUGGAGGACCGAGGCACGGGCACGGUGGGCCGAGCACAGAACUACCAGAAGCGCUUCCAGAACCUGAACUGGCGCAGCCACAACAACCUCCGCAUCACACGCAUCCUCAAGUCGCUGGGUGAGCUGGGCCUCGAGCACUUCCAGGCGCCGCUGGUCCGCUUCUUCCUGGAGGAGACGCUGGUGCGGCGGGAGCUGCCGGGGGUGCGGCAGAGUGCCCUGGACUACUUCAUGUUCGCCGUGCGCUGCCGACACCAGCGCCGCCAGCUGGUGCACUUCGCCUGGGAGCACUUCCGGCCCCGCUGCAAGUUCGUCUGGGGGCCCCAAGACAAGCUGCGGAGGUUCAAGCCCAGCUCUCUGCCCCAUCCGCUCGAGGGCUCCAGGAAGGUGGAGGAGGAAGGAAGCCCCGGGGACCCCGACCACGAGGCCAGCACCCAGGGUCGGACCUGUGGGCCAGAGCAUAGCAAGGGUGGGGGCAGGGUGGACGAGGGGCCCCAGCCACGGAGCGUGGAGCCCCAGGAUGCGGGACCCCUGGAGAGGAGCCAGGGGGAUGAGGCAGGGGGCCACGGGGAAGAUAGGCCGGAGCCCUUAAGCCCCAAAGAGAGCAAGAAGAGGAAGCUGGAGCUGAGCCGGCGGGAGCAGCCGCCCACAGAGCCAGGCCCUCAGAGUGCCUCAGAGGUGGAGAAGAUCGCUCUGAAUUUGGAGGGGUGUGCCCUCAGCCAGGGCAGCCUCAGGACGGGGACCCAGGAAGUGGGCGGUCAGGACCCUGGGGAGGCAGUGCAGCCCUGCCGCCAACCCCUGGGAGCCAGGGUGGCCGACAAGGUGAGGAAGCGGAGGAAGGUGGAUGAGGGUGCUGGGGACAGUGCUGCGGUGGCCAGUGGUGGUGCCCAGACCUUGGCCCUUGCCGGGUCCCCUGCCCCAUCGGGGCACCCCAAGGCUGGACACAGUGAGAACGGGGUUGAGGAGGACACAGAAGGUCGAACGGGGCCCAAAGAAGGUACCCCUGGGAGCCCAUCGGAGACCCCAGGCCCCAGCCCAGCAGGACCUGCAGGGGACGAGCCAGCCGAGAGCCCAUCGGAGACCCCAGGCCCCCGCCCAGCAGGACCUGCAGGGGACGAGCCAGCCGAGAGCCCAUCGGAGACCCCAGGCCCCCGCCCGGCAGGACCUGCAGGGGACGAGCCAGCCGAGAGCCCAUCGGAGACCCCAGGCCCCAGCCCGGCAGGACCUACAAGGGAUGAGCCAGCCGAGAGCCCAUCGGAGACCCCAGGCCCCCGCCCGGCAGGACCUGCAGGGGACGAGCCAGCCGAGAGCCCAUCGGAGACCCCAGGCCCCCGCCCGGCAGGACCUGCAGGGGACGAGCCAGCCGAGAGCCCAUCGGAGACCCCAGGCCCCAGCCCGGCAGGACCUACAAGGGAUGAGCCAGCCAAGGCGGGGGAGGCAGCAGAGUUGCAGGACGCAGAGGUGGAGUCUUCUGCCAAGUCUGGGAAGCCUUAAGGAAAGGAGUGCCCGUCGGCGUCUUGGUCCUCCUGUCCCUGCUGCAGGGGCUGGGGCCUCCGGAGCUGCUGCGGGCUCCCCUCAGGCUCUGCUUCGUGACCCGUGACCCAUGACCCACAGUGCUGGCCUCCUGUGGGGCCACUAUAGCAGCCACCAGAAGCCGCGAGGCCCUCAGGGAAGCCCAAGGCCUGCAGAAGCCUCCUGGCCUGGCUGUGUCUUCCCCACCCAGCUCUCCCCUGCGCCCCUGUCUUUGUAAAUUGACCCUUCUGGAGUGGGGGGCGGCGGGCAGGGCUGCUUUUCUUAGUCUGAUACCAAGCAAGGCCUUUUCUGAAUAAAUUCAUUUGACUUUGA